CGUCCCCGCUGUGGCUUUGGCUGCCUGUCUUACUCAAGUUUUCAUUAUCUUCCUGGGCAGCUGAUUGGCACGUUAGUAAAACGCAGCAGGACUAGCUUUCUCACUUAUUAGUUCUCUAACUUUAGGCAAAUCAUUUAACGUCUCUGAUCCUCAGUGAACUUGCUUGAAACUAGCUUUCCUCAUCUGUUGAAUGAGGGUGGUAAUACCAUGAGCCCCAGGCCCACACUGAAAGCAUGUCGAUCCAGGAGAACAUAUCAUCCCUGCAGCUUCGGUCAUGGGUCUCUAAGUCCCAAAGAGACUUAGCAAAGUCCAUCCUGAUUGGGGCUCCAGGAGGGCCAGCGGGGUAUCUGCGGCGGGCCAGUGUGGCCCAACUGACCCAGGAGCUGGGCACUGCCUUCUUCCAGCAGCAGCAGCUGCCAGCUGCUAUGGCAGACACCUUCCUGGAACACCUCUGCCUACUGGACAUUGACUCCGAGCCCGUGGCUGCUCGCAGUACCAGCAUCAUUGCCACCAUCGGGCCAGCAUCUCGCUCCGUGGAGCGCCUCAAGGAGAUGAUCAAGGCCGGGAUGAACAUUGCGCGACUCAACUUCUCCCACGGCUCCCACGAGUACCAUGCUGAGUCCAUCGCCAACGUCCGGGAGGCGGUGGAGAGCUUUGCAGGUUCCCCACUCAGCUACCGGCCCGUGGCCAUCGCCCUGGACACCAAGGGACCGGAGAUCCGCACUGGGAUCCUGCAGGGGGGUCCAGAGUCGGAAGUGGAGCUGGUGAAGGGCUCCCAGGUGCUGGUGACUGUGGACCCCGCGUUCCGGACGCGGGGGAACGCGAACACCGUGUGGGUGGACUACCCCAAUAUUGUCCGGGUCGUGCCGGUGGGGGGCCGCAUCUACAUUGACGACGGGCUCAUCUCCCUAGUGGUCCAGAAAAUCGGCCCAGAGGGACUGGUGACCCAAGUGGAGAACGGCGGCGUCCUGGGCAGCCGGAAGGGCGUGAACUUGCCAGGGGCCCAGGUGGACUUGCCCGGGCUGUCCGAGCAGGACGUCCGAGACCUGCGCUUCGGGGUGGAGCAUGGGGUGGACAUCGUCUUUGCCUCCUUUGUGCGGAAAGCCAGCGACGUGGCUGCCGUCAGGGCUGCUCUGGGUCCGGAAGGACACGGCAUCAAGAUCAUCAGCAAAAUUGAGAACCACGAAGGCGUGAAGAGGUUUGAUGAAAUCCUGGAGGUGAGCGACGGCAUCAUGGUGGCACGGGGGGACCUAGGCAUCGAGAUCCCAGCAGAGAAGGUUUUCCUGGCUCAGAAGAUGAUGAUUGGGCGCUGCAACUUGGCGGGCAAGCCUGUUGUCUGUGCCACACAGAUGCUGGAGAGCAUGAUUACCAAGCCCCGGCCAACGAGGGCAGAGACAAGCGAUGUCGCCAAUGCUGUGCUGGAUGGGGCUGACUGCAUCAUGCUGUCAGGGGAGACUGCCAAGGGCAACUUCCCUGUGGAAGCGGUGAAGAUGCAGCAUGCGAUUGCCCGGGAGGCAGAGGCCGCAGUGUACCACCGGCAGCUGUUUGAGGAGCUACGUCGGGCAGCGCCACUAAGCCGUGAUCCCACUGAGGUCACCGCCAUUGGUGCUGUGGAGGCUGCCUUCAAGUGCUGUGCUGCUGCCAUCAUUGUGCUGACCACAACUGGCCGCUCAGCCCAGCUUCUGUCUCGGUACCGACCUCGGGCAGCAGUCAUUGCUGUCACCCGCUCUGCCCAGGCUGCCCGCCAGGUCCACUUAUGCCGAGGAGUCUUCCCCUUGCUUUACCGUGAACCUCCAGAAGCCAUCUGGGCAGAUGAUGUAGAUCGCCGGGUGCAAUUUGGCAUUGAAAGUGGAAAGCUCCGUGGCUUCCUCCGUGUUGGAGACCUGGUGAUUGUGGUGACAGGCUGGCGACCUGGCUCCGGCUACACCAACAUCAUGCGGGUGCUAAGCAUAUCCUGAGACGCCCCUCCCUCCUCUGGCCCAGCCUACCCUUGUACCCCAUCCCUUCCUCCCCAGUCUACGUUCUCCAGCCCACACCCCUCCAAAGCCCCACCUUUAAGUCCUCUCUUCUCUAUUCCUGACCCUCCCUACCUGAGGCCUAUCUGAGACUAUAACUGUCAUCUAGCCCCUUCGAGGUUGCCCCUUCCCCAUCUCCAUUUCACACAGGUCCUGAAAGUCUGUGUCCAAUUAUGCACUGGCCACCCAACAGCACCAAUUGUACAUUCCCUGCAUCCAAUCUGCUCAGCAGGCCCUAAGAUGCCUUGAGUCUUUAAUCCCAGUUUGGCUGGUUAAUUCCAUAACCCCAGGCAUCCCAUCCCUUGGGGUGGGGGAGAGGGGAGACAGGGCAAUCUUGUCCACAGUCUCCCAUUCUCAUAUGUAGCCCUCAUGAUAAUCUGGGCAUCUCGUGCCAGGGCAGGCUACCCCUUCAUGGUGACUAACAGUUACAUGAAAGUCCACGCUUUUGGGAAAACUGGGUGGGAUGGAUGCUGGGGAGAAGUGAGGGCUGGGCAGCUGAUUUUGUCACUGUCUUCACAACCUCCGUGCUGGGCUUGUAGACCACUGUCCUGGCUGCUCUCAUGCCUGCCUGAUACCCUGCUUGGUCAAAUCCCCGGCUGCUUCCUUCUGCACCCAGAAAUUCCUUCCCACUCAUGUUGUUCCCACACACAAACCAAGAGCCAAAAAUGAGUGUGUCUAUUUUAUAUUUAAACCCAGCUGUUUGGAAGCAAUUAUAAAACUUCUCCCACACACCAAGAACCCCAGAACUCCCCACCCAGAAGGAAAGGAGACUUAGGGUCCUGGUCCCACAGUCUUUAAUGCUGUAGAGUAGGAGAGGGGACAGGCAGAGUGAGGGUGGUAAAGGACUACUCUUGUCCCUGAGAAGGCAGAGGUGCUGGCUGGCCUGCCCUUCCCCAGGCUUGGAUACCUUGGGCCUUUCCCUUAUUCCUGCACCAACAGCAAACUCAGAAGGAAAAAACAAAACAAAACUCUAAAGGUAAACGCGGUCCUUCUCCCUCUCUCAUGUGGCUCCUCCUGCCCCUACCUGGGAGAAGGUUCAAGUAUUGCGCUGAUGGGUUUGGGCAAGGACCACAGAGGCUGGCAUGGAGAGGCCCUGCCUCCUCCUACUCCUCCUGUCUCCUUACCUGAAAAGGAGGGGAGGGAUGGAUAAAGGAAUGGGUAAACAAAAUUAAUUGGUAACACAUAAAGUUAGUAAAUGAAUAAAUACAAUUAAAUAAAUGAA